AGUCAGGCAGCGGGAGCCGCCGGGAGCGGAUGGCGGCGGCCGUAGCGGCUCCACUCGCCGCCGGGGGUGAGGAGGCGGCAGCCACGACCUCCGUGCCCGGGUCUCCAGGUCUGCCGGGGAGACGCAGUGCAGAGCGGGCCCUAGAGGAGGCCGUGGCCACCGGGACCCUGAACCUGUCUAACCGGCGCUUGAAGCACUUCCCCCGGGGCGCGGCCCGUAGCUACGACCUGUCAGACAUCACCCAGGCUGACCUGUCCCGGAACCGGUUUCCCGAGGUGCCCGAGGCGGCGUGCCAGCUGGUGUCCCUGGAGGGCCUGAGCCUCUACCACAAUUGCCUGAGAUGCCUGAACCCAGCCUUGGGGAAUCUCACAGCCCUCACCUACCUCAACCUCAGCCGAAACCAGCUGUCGCUGCUGCCACCCUACAUCUGCCAGCUGCCCCUGAGGGUCCUCAUCGUCAGCAACAACAAGCUGGGAGCCCUGCCCCCUGACAUCGGCACCCUGGGAAGCCUGCGACAGCUUGACGUGAGCAGCAACGAGCUCCAAUCCCUGCCCUCGGAACUGUGUGGCCUCUCUUCCCUGCGGGACCUCAAUGUCCGGAGGAACCAGCUCAGUACGCUGCCCGAAGAGCUGGGGGACCUCCCUCUGGUCCGCCUGGAUUUCUCCUGUAACCGCGUCUCCCGAAUCCCAGUCUCCUUCUGCCGCCUGAGGCACCUGCAGGUCAUUCUGCUGGACAGCAACCCUCUGCAGAGUCCACCUGCCCAGAGGCCGGGCAGCGUGGGUCGGCCCUGGGGGACCUGGCCCCUUCUCGGCCCCCGAGUUUCAGUCCCUGGAGGAUGGGGGGCUGUUGUCCAGCAUCAGGCUGACCAGAUCCGCCUGGCUGGCCCCAGCCCUGCAGAGGAUCUAUUUCCGGGACAUCGGUACGAUGGUGGGCUGGACUCAGGCUUCCACAGCGUUGAUAGUGGCAGCAAGAGGUGGUCUGGAAAUGAGUCAACAGAUGAAUUUUCAGAGCUGUCAUUCCGGAUCUCAGAGCUGGCCCGGGAGCCCCGGGGACCCAGAGAACGCAAGGAGGAUGGCUCAGCGGACGGAGACCCUGUGCAGAUUGACUUCAUCGACAGCCAUGUCCCCGGGGAGGAUGAAGAGCGAGGCACUGUGGAGGAGCAGCGACCACCCGAAUUAAGCCCUGGGGCAGGGGACAGGGAGAGGGCACCAAGCAGCAGGCGGGAGGAGCCGGCAGGGGAGGAGCGGCGGCGCCCGGACACCUUGCAGCUGUGGCAGGAGCGGGAACGGCGGCAGCAGCAGCAGAGCGGGGCGUGGGGGGCCCCGAGGAAGGAUAGCCUCUUGAAGCCAGGGCUCAGGGCUGUUGUGGGAGGGGCCGCCGCCGUGUCCACUCAAGCCAUGCACAACGGCUCGCCUAAGUCCAGUGCCUCCCAAGCAGGGGCUGCAGCGGGGCAGGGAGCCCCCGCCCCUGCCCCUGCCUCCCAAGAGCCCCUUCCCAUAGCUGGACCAGCGACAGCACCUGCUCCACGGCCACUUGGCUCCAUUCAGAGACCAAACAGCUUCCUCUUCCGUUCCUCCUCUCAGAGUGGCUCAGGCCCUUCCUCACCAGACUCUGUCCUGAGACCUCGGCGGUACCCCCAGGUUCCAGAUGAGAAGGACUUAAUGACUCAGCUGCGCCAGGUCCUUGAGUCCCGGCUGCAGCGGCCCCUGCCUGAGGACCUGGCCGAGGCUCUGGCCAGUGGGGUCAUCCUGUGCCAGCUGGCCAACCAGCUACGGCCGCGCUCCGUGCCCUUCAUCCAUGUGCCCUCCCCUGCUGUGCCAAAACUCAGUGCCCUCAAGGCUCGGAAGAAUGUGGAGAGUUUUCUAGAAGCCUGUCGAAAAAUGGGGGUGCCUGAGGCUGACCUGUGCUCGCCCUCGGAUCUCCUCCAGGGCACUGCCCGGGGGCUGCGGACCGCGCUGGAGGCCGUGAAGCGGGUGGGGGGCAAGGCCCUACCGCCCCUCUGGCCCCCCUCUGGUCUGGGCGGCUUCGUCGUCUUCUACGUGGUCCUCAUGCUGCUGCUCUAUGUCACCUACACUCGGCUCCUGGGUUCCUAGGCCCCAAAAUCGGCCCUCCCUCACCCCUUUCCCUUCCUCUCUAUUUAUAAGGUCCCUGCUCCACCCGACCCCACCUGCGGUGCCUUCAGCCCCAACCAAAGACACUAGUGCACCCCCUUCACAGACACUGACCUCAGAGGCCCCACUCUGGUGCCCCCAGACCCUGGGCCCCCAGCCUCUGGCCUCCCUCCAGUAGCCCCACGAGUCCCCACCUCUCAGUGCUGACGGUGCCUUCAUGUCCCCGCCGGCCCUGCCCCUGCCCUCUGUACCCCGUGAGGGGUGGCAGGAGCUGGAGUCUCCCCCUUCCUCCUGUGCCCUCCCCUUCCCCCCCCAACAGCUGCUAUGGGGGGGCUAAAUUAUCUCUAUUUUGUAGAGAGGAUCUAUAUUUGUAGGGGUUCGGGGCCCAGGCCGGGUCCCUAUCUCUGUGUAUAAACUGUACAGACCGUGGCCGCCCUGCCUGUGUGUGUGUGUGUGCGCGCGCGCGCGCGUCUGCUCCGCGUGUUGGUGGCUGUGGCCAUGGCUCUGUGCCCACCAGCAUCUCCCUCCUGAGAUGCCGGCCUCUCAUGCUCCCGGAGCGUCCGCCAACCCCCCGUGUCACCUCCCUUCUGUUAUCGCUGACAGCUUUCUUGCGUCUCAUUUGUCGCCGAGCCCCGAGCGCACGGUGAUGCUCGGGUCUGCCCCCGACCCCCUGCCACAGGCCGGAAGCCGCAGGGGGCACCGUGGGGAAGCUAACCCGGCCCCUUCCCCCAGGAGUCACUGUGCCAGCCCCACCACAUCCUGGAAGAGGAGGGGGCCCCGGGAAGGGGCCUCCCCUACAUCGCUGCUGUCGUCCACGCCCUGCUGGACCGGCCUUAGGGGUGAAGGUGGGGGCACAGGGCCCACCCCGCCCGGGACCCCGGGAGCAGAAGACGCGCCUGGGCUCCGCGCUCUCAGAGAAGCACGUGGUGAGGGUGGCCUGGGCCUGGGCACCCUUGGCCUGCCGGCCUGGCUGCCUCUGGGGUCGAGGGUCUGGGUGGAAGGACCGCGGGUGUCGCAGGUGUCGUGUCAGCCGCAAUAAACAGAAGCCAGAAGCCCUCUGGGUGGCCCUCAGGUGUAA